CUCUCUUUCACUGCAAGGCGGCGGCAGGAGAGGUUGUGGUGCUAGUUUCUCUAAGCCAUCCAGUGCCAUCCUCGUCGCUGCAGCGACACACGCUCUCGCCGCCGCCAUGACUGAGCAGAUGACCCUUCGUGGCACCCUCAAGGGCCACAACGGCUGGGUAACCCAGAUCGCUACUACCCCGCAGUUCCCGGACAUGAUCCUCUCCGCCUCUCGAGAUAAGACCAUCAUCAUGUGGAAACUGACCAGGGAUGAGACCAACUAUGGAAUUCCACAGCGUGCUCUGCGGGGUCACUCCCACUUUGUUAGUGAUGUGGUUAUCUCCUCAGAUGGCCAGUUUGCCCUCUCAGGCUCCUGGGAUGGAACCCUGCGCCUCUGGGAUCUCACAACGGGCACCACCACGAGGCGAUUUGUGGGCCAUACCAAGGAUGUGCUGAGUGUGGCCUUCUCCUCUGACAACCGGCAGAUUGUCUCUGGAUCUCGAGAUAAAACCAUCAAGCUAUGGAAUACCCUGGGUGUGUGCAAAUACACUGUCCAGGAUGAGAGCCACUCAGAGUGGGUGUCUUGUGUCCGCUUCUCGCCCAACAGCAGCAACCCUAUCAUCGUCUCCUGUGGCUGGGACAAGCUGGUCAAGGUAUGGAACCUGGCUAACUGCAAGCUGAAGACCAACCACAUUGGCCACACAGGCUAUCUGAACACGGUGACUGUCUCUCCAGAUGGAUCCCUCUGUGCUUCUGGAGGCAAGGAUGGCCAGGCCAUGUUAUGGGAUCUCAACGAAGGCAAACACCUUUACACGCUAGAUGGUGGGGACAUCAUCAACGCCCUGUGCUUCAGCCCUAACCGCUACUGGCUGUGUGCUGCCACAGGCCCCAGCAUCAAGAUCUGGGAUUUAGAGGGAAAGAUCAUUGUAGAUGAACUGAAGCAAGAAGUUAUCAGUACCAGCAGCAAGGCAGAACCACCCCAGUGCACCUCCCUGGCCUGGUCUGCUGAUGGCCAGACUCUGUUUGCUGGCUACACGGACAACCUGGUGCGAGUGUGGCAGGUGACCAUUGGCACACGCUAGAAGUUUAUGGCAGAGCUUUACAAAUAAAAAAAAAACUGGCUUUUCUGACUUUUAGGUUUUUUUUUCUUAUAUGCAAAAAA